ACAUUGCCAGCAUCUUCUCUCCUCACUCACCCUUCCUGGUGCUUUGGGCUCUCCUUCCUUCUCAGACAAGAUGUCUUAUCAGAAAAAGCAGCCCACCCCUCAGCCCCCAGUGGACUGCGUGAAGACCUCUGGCGGCGGUGGCGGUGGCGGCGGCAGCGGCGGUGGUGGCUGCGGCUUCUUCGGCGGCGGCGGCUCAGGGGGCGGUAGCAGCGGUUCUGGCUGCGGCUACUCCGGCGGCGGUGGCUACUCUGGCGGCGGCUGCGGCGGGGGCUCCUCCGGCGGCGGGGGCGGGGGCGGCAUUGGAGGCUGCGGAGGGGGCUCCGGUGGGAGCGUCAAGUACUCCGGAGGCGGCGGCUCCUCCGGCGGGGGCUCUGGCUGUUUCUCCAGCGGUGGGGGCGGCUCCGGCUGCUUCUCCUCCGGUGGCGGCGGCUCCUCCGGGGGCGGCUCCGGCUGCUUCUCCAGCGGUGGGGGCGGCUCCUCCGGGGGCGGCUCCGGCUGCUUCUCCUCCGGCGGCGGCGGCUUCUCGGGCCAGGCGGUCCAGUGCCAGAGCUACGGAGGCGUCUCUAGCGGCGGCUCCUCCGGGGGCGGCUCCGGCUGCUUCUCCAGCGGCGGGGGCGGCGGCUCUGUCUGCGGCUACUCUGGCGGCGGCUCUGGCUGCGGCGGAGGCUCCUCUGGCGGCAGCGGCUCCGGCUACGUCUCCUCGCAGCAGGUCACUCAGACCUCGUGCGCGCCCCAGCCGAGUUACGGAGGGGGGUCGUCCGGCGGCGGCGGCAGCGGCGGAAGCGGCUGCUUCUCCAGCGGCGGGGGCGGCGGGAGCUCCGGCUGCGGCGGCGGCUCCUCCGGGAUUGGCAGCGGCUGCAUCAUCAGUGGCGGGGGCUCCGUCUGCGGAGGUGGUUCCUCUGGAGGCGGCGGCGGCGGCUCCUCCGUGGGUGGCUCCGGGAGUGGCAAGGGCGUCCCGAUCUGCCACCAGACCCAGCAGAAGCAGGCGCCUACCUGGCCGUCCAAAUAGAUCCCCCAGGGUACCACGGAGGCGAAGGAGUUGGAGGUGUUUUCCAGGGGCACCGAUGGGCUUAGAGCUCUCAUGAUGCUACCCGAGGUUUGCAAAUCCUUCAUGUCUUAACCUACCUGGAAGAAGCCAUUGAGCUCUCCGGCUGCAUCUAGUUCUGCUGUUUAGCCUCUUUGGUUUCUGUACAACUACCUCCCAACCCCAGUGCCUCAGUCAAUAAAUUUGCAAAUUCAUGAGAA